CUGCCUGCCUCGGCCUCCCAAAGUGCUGGGAUUAUAAGCGUGAGCCACCUCGCCCAGCGGGUCUGUUUCUGAUGGGUCAUUCUUGCAGGUUGAACAAGUUUUCCAAAAUGUGGUGGUUUGUCCUCAGUGGUGGCAAAGUGUCAGCUGAGAGUAAGUAGGGAUUGUUCUAUCUGCCUUGGCUCUCAGGCGAAGGUCAGGCAUAGCUGGAGGACAGAAUCCUUUUCUUCUUCUUCUUUUCUUUUCUUUUCUUUUUUUUUUUUUUUUGAGACAAGGUCUCACUCUGUAGCCCGGGCUAGAGCACAGUGGAACAAUCACUGCUUACUGCAGCCGUGACUUCCUGGGCUCAAGUGAUUCUCCUGCCUCAGUCUCCCCAGUAGCUGGGACUACAUACAUGCACCAUGCCCAGCUAAUUUUUGUAUUUUUUGUAGAGAUGGGGUUUUACCAUGUUGGCCAGGCUAUUCCUGGGCUCAAAUAAUCCACCUGUCUCUGCCUCCCAAAGUGCUGGGAUUACAGGCAGAGCCCCCAUGCCUGGCACAGAAUCCUGUAAGAACACUAUAAACUAACUCUAUUAAGCAUCUCCUGCCUUUGAUUAGAUACCUACUGUAAACCAGGUACAGUGACAUGAAUUUGGUAAACUUGUAUCAUUAAUCUGUAUAAUCAUGUGAUAUGGAUAGUAUUUCUCCCAGUUUACAAGUGAAUGAAACAGAGGCUCAGAGAGGUGCAGUAAGGUGCCCAAGGUCACACAUCCUGAAAGUUGCAGAGCUGAAUUUUAAUCCAGGAAGGUCUGGUUCCCAAACCUGUGACAUUGUGAUCCAACAUGCUAAGUUUCCUCGAGGAGACCUUGGGAAUCACCUCCAUCAAUCCAACUGCUUUGAAGAUGAGAAAAGAAAGGCCCGGAUGGUCAGGCAAGGUGGCUCAUGUCUAUAAUCCCAACAUUUUGGGAGGCUGAGGUGGAAGGACUGCUUGAGGCCAGGAGUUUGAGACCAGCCUGAGCAAUAUAGCAAGACACUAUCUAUAUUUUUUUAAUAGAAAUCAAAGAAAGAAAAGAAAGGCCUUAGAUAGGAAAAGGGACCUGCCUAAAGUCACUCAGUAGCAGGACAAGGACUAGAACCUAGGCUUCCCUACUCCCAGUUGGGGAUAAAAACGGUGAGGCUUGUGGCAUCAAAUCUCAGCUUCCCACUGUAGGUGUGGUAGCCACAGGCAGGGUAUCAUUCUCUUCCUUACCUCCAGCUCUGAGAGAUUUAAACCCAGCAGCAACGUGGGACCAGCCGCUACUGUGGCUUCUUUCACUUCACGCUUUCACUUCAGGUUAGAAAAACCCCCAGGCACACCUUUUCUGAGCAGGUUCUCAGGUCCCAAGUUUCCCUUCCCAGAUGCUCAGUAUGAACCAGGCUGUAGGCUGCAGCCCCUAACACCAGCCCCACCAUGGACGCUCCCUAUGUGAAGUGCCAUAUGGUUUCUGAACAGUGGUAUUUUUGUUAGGUGAAGAAAGGACUUGGUCAUGGUGGUUCACUUUUUUCUUUUUCUUCUUCUUUAUUUAUUUAUUUAUUUUUUUAAACUGAAUCUAGCUUUAUUGCCCAGGCUGGAGUGCAGUGGCGCAAUCUCAGCUCACUGCAACCUCUGCCUCCUGGGUUCAAGUGAUUCUCGUACUUCAGCCUCCCGAAUAGCUGGGAUUACAGGCACCUGCCCCCACUCCUGGCUAAUUUUUGUAUUUUUAGUAGACAGGGUUUCACCGUGUUGGCCAGGCUGGUCUCAAACUCCUGACCUCAAGUGAUCUGCCCUCCUCGGCCUCCCAAAGUGCUGGGAUUACAGGCGUGAGCCACCGCGCCUGGCCUUUUUUCUUUUUUAAUCAGGCAGCCCAGAAUAGGUUCAGAAAGACUCCCGCUUCUCUUUUACUCUUACAUCUGUACAGCAUCAGGUCACAAAAUGUUUUUGCAUGCAUCGGUGAUUCUUAAUAUUCAGAACUCUGCUGGCACACUGAUAAAAAGUGUGAAUCCUUCUACCCCAACCAAAACAUGCACAGACAUAAAGUCUUAAAUAUGCCUCGAAAGGACCGAUACUCCCAUCCAAGCCUACCCAUGGACCCAGGGUAAGAAGCUAUGAUGGAGGUCAUCAGCCCAUUUGGCAUCUCAAGGAGAAUGGCAUAGCAAAGCCUUCUAGACAAGCUCAGUGGAAUCUGAAGGGCCCACCCCAUGGAGGAAUGCUGGGUGACAGAGAUAGCCAAUGGCUCCAAGGAUGGCUUGGAUUCCAACCCUAUGAAGGAUUACAUGAUCCUGAGUGGUCCCCAGAAGACAGCUGUUGCUGUGUUGUGCACUCUUCUGGGCCUGCUAAGUGCCCUGGAGAACGUGGCUGUGCUCUAUCUGAUCCUGUCCUCCCACCAACUCCGCCGGAAGCCCUCAUACCUGUUCAUUGGCAGCUUGGCUGGGGCUGACUUCCUGGCCAGUGUGGUCUUUGCAUGCAGCUUUGUGAAUUUCCAUGUUUUCCAUGGUGUGGAUUCCAAGGCUGUCUUCCUGCUGAAGAUUGGCAGCGUGACUAUGACCUUCACAGCCUCUGUGGGUAGCCUCCUGCUGACCGCCAUUGACCGAUACCUCUGCCUGCGCUAUCCACCUUCCUACAAAGCUCUGCUCACCCGUGGAAGGGCACUGGUGACCCUGGGCAUCAUGUGGGUCCUCUCAGCACUAGUCUCCUACCUGCCCCUCAUGGGAUGGACUUGCUGUCCCAGGCCCUGCUCUGAGCUUUUCCCACUGAUCCCCAAUGACUACCUGCUGAGCUGGCUCCUGUUCAUCGCCUUCCUCUUUUCCGGAAUCAUCUACACCUAUGGGCAUGUUCUCUGGAAGGCCCAUCAGCAUGUGGCCAGCUUGUCUGGCCACCAGGACAGGCAGGUGCCAGGAAUGGCCCGAAUGAGGCUGGAUGUGAGGUUGGCCAAGACCCUAGGGCUAGUGUUGGCUGUGCUCCUCAUCUGUUGGUUCCCAGUGCUGGCCCUCAUGGCCCACAGCCUGGCCACUACGCUCAGUGACCAGGUCAAGAAGGCCUUUGCUUUCUGCUCCAUGCUGUGCCUCAUCAACUCCAUGGUCAACCCUGUCAUCUAUGCUCUACGGAGUGGAGAGAUCCGCUCCUCUGCCCAUCACUGCCUGGCUCACUGGAAGAAGUGUGUGAGGGGCCUUGGGUCAGAGGCAAAAGAAGAAGCCCCGAGAUCCUCAGUCACCGAGACAGAGGCUGAUGGGAAAAUCACUCCGUGGCCAGAUUCCAGAGAUCUAGACCUCUCUGAUUGCUGAUGAGGCCUCUUCCCAAUUUAAACAACUCAAGUCAGAAAUCAGUUCACUCCCUGGAAGAGAGAGAGGGGUCUUGGCACUCUCUUCUUACUUAAACCAGUCCCAGACACCUAGACACGGACCCCUUUUUGCUGAUGAGUGUUGGGACUGACUCCUGGAAGACAGCCUGGCCUUGCCCACCUGCACACAGUCUGUUGGAUAGGUAGGGCCACGAGGAGUAGCCAGGUAGGCGAGACACAAAAGGCCUGGGACAGGGUCAGUACAAGUCAGGUCAGGCUUCAUGCCUGCAUCCUCCAGAGACCACAGGAGCCAAAGCGAGCCUCCAGGCCCAGCAAUGAGGGACUUGGGAGAAAUCUGAGAAGAAUGGGUUGUUCUCUUGGGAAGUCAGGGUAUCAGAUGGGAUGGACAUCCAGGUCUUCUCUCUGCCUAAUUGUCAAGGCCUCCUUGGCUCUGGAGCUAUGAAAGGCCCCACUUUCAAGUCACCCUUGCCACUGAGGACCGAGGACUAUGCUAUGAUGAGGAUUAAGGUGUUGACUUGCCUCUUUCAGAGAUAAAUGACAAGCCUUCAGUUUGGGGCAUCCUGUUGUUUGGGCGAGGACCCUCUCUGAUAUUCUGAUAAUCCCCACCUGUAACCUCAGGUCCCUGGAAAUACAGAGGAGGCUGGGAUCGCCUGAGACACAAAAAUCUUUGGAGAAUUUUCUUGACCCUCUGAAGUCCUUCCAGCAGCAGUCCUGGUGGUGCUGCUGGAAGCAGGCAAUGUCCUAGUCUAACCUAACUCGAAGAAAAAAAGGAAGAUAUUCACAAAGAUUGUAUAAAUCUCCAAACUGUUCCCCUAUCUGCCCCCAAUUCAGCUCCCUUGCCUCCUCCACACCCCUAUUACAUAUAAUAAGCAGAGCAAGUGGGAGGAGGGGAAAUGUCCUUCCUAUAUGCCAGGUAUGGGGCUGACAUUUCAGUCUAUUGACCCCAGCUAGAAUAUAGCUCCAUGAUUUUAAAGAUCUCAGGGGCCAGGCAUGGUAGCUCAUGCCUGUAAUCCCAGCACUUUGGGAGGCCAAGGCAGGUGGAUCACCUGAGGUCAGGAGUUUGAGACCAGCCUGACCAAUAUGGUGAAACCCUGUCUCUACUAAAAAUACAAAAAUUAGCAGGGCAUGGUGGCAGGCACCUGUAGUCCCAGCUACUCGGGAGGCUGAGACAGGAGAAUUGCUUGAACCCUGGAGGCAGAGGUUGCAGUGAGCCGAGAUUGCACCACUGCACUCCAGCCUGGGUGACAGAGCAAGACUGUCUCAAAAAAAUAAAAUAAAAUAGAUCCCAGGGUACUCAUUUUUCAUAUGAGGGAGGCUGGGUUCCUCCCAGAGGAGCCUAAAACAGCCAACAAGAGAAAUUGUUGGCGGCAGGAAGAUUGCAGAGGAAUUCUAAUGCAAUUAUUUGGGACCUCAAAUGGAAUAAAAUGAAAGAUAUUGGUUAAACAUGUCUUCGUUUAAUACUUUCAAGACAAAAUAUCCACUAGCUAUUCACUUAUUCAUUCAUCUCAUAAACAUGAGCCAGGCUCUGUGCAGGGUCCUGAGUACCCAGCCAUAAAUGAGACUGUGCCCCUGUCUCAUGGGGCUUACAGUCUAUAUCCUGCUUGCAAGACAGCCAAUAAGUCAAUAAAGAAGAUAAUUACAGGCAGUACAACAAAGGAAAUAUGCAGGUUCAUGUCAUGUAAUAGGGAUUAAUUGAGUUAACUCAAUAAACGGUAGGAUAGACCUACCAUGUGCCGGCUCACUUUUAUUGAGCCUUUACUAUGUGCCAGGCAGGGGGCUAAGUGUUUUUAAAUGCCUUAUUUCACUUCAUGUUUCCCAACAACCUAAUAAGAAGGUCUUAGUUAUCUUCAUUUUACAGAUGUGGCAACCUCAAAGAUGCAAAGUCACUUGUCUAAGGUCACCCUGCUAAGUACCAGAGCUGAGGUCUCCAACCUAGUUCUGUUUGACUUCAAAGCCUGCCCUCUUAACCACUAACCUUUUGUCCUAGUUCAGUCAAAUUCUGCUUGAUUAUUGCUCAUUAGGGAUAAUAUUAGCUAUCUGUAGCAUCAGAUUGCUGCAAAGUUAACUCAUCGUAGAUUCUCAAUAUACUCCAUUUUAUUAAAUGGCCCCGUAUUAAUCUCCUGUAAUAAAUUUCACAAAUCCAGUGGCUUAUCAACAGAAAUUUACUGUCUCAUAAUUCUGGAGGCCAGAAGUCAAAAUCAAGAUGUGGUAGGGCCCUGCUCCCUCCAAAAGUUUAAGGGGAGAAUUAUUCCUUGACUCUUUCAACUUCUGGCAGUCCCUGUCAUUCCUUGGCUUGUGGAAACAUCACUCCUACCUCUGACUCUGUCUUCAUAUGGCAUUUCCUCUGUGUCUCUUGGUGUCUUUUUUUUUUUUUUUUUUUUUUUUGAGACGGAAUCUCAUUCUGUUGUCCAGGCAGGAGUGCAGUGACAUGAUCUUGGCUCACUGCAACCUCCACCUCUCAGGUUCAAGUGAUUCUCCUGCCUCAGCCUCCCAAAUAGCUGGGACUACAGGCACCCGCCACCACACUCAGCUAAUUUUUGUAUUUUUAGUAGAGAUGGGGUUUCACCAUCUUGCCCAGGCUGGUCUUGAACUCCUGACCUCAAGUGAUCCGCCCACCUUGGCCUCCUAAAUUGCUGGGAUUACAGACGUGAGCCACCAUACCCGGCCUGGUGUCUUUUUUAAAGAAUAUCAGUCACUGGAUUUGGGCCCACCCUAAUCCUAAUAGUAUGACUUCAUCUUAAUUUAACCAAUUAUAUCUGUAGAGACCCUGUUUCCAAAUAAGGUCACAUUCACAGAUUCCAGGUGGACAAGAAGUUUAGGCGGACACUAUUCAACUCAGUACAGACCCAGGAACAAAGUCCACCCACUGGGCUGUGUUGAGUGGCAGUCACUAGUUUAUCCUCCCUCAACAAGAUGAGCUCCAGGUUGACCUCUGCAUCCCCAGUGCUCAGUCAGGACCCAGCAGAGCAUCUGAAGGGAUCUGGUCAAUAUGUGUGGAACUGAACUGUUUCUGAAAAGCUCUGACGUAUGUUUUGGAAAAUCAAAUCUUGUUUUAAUCCAGACACCAAUCUUUUUGUAAGGCAAACAAGUAGCAUAAAUGUUUAAAAGUGAAUUUGCAUGUUUAUAUACUGUCAUUCCUUAAAGUUGAAGCAUGCCUUUCUUUAUUCAUCGGUGGAAUCCUUUCUCAUUUUGGCAAAGAAAAUGCCCAAGUGCCUGGCACAAACAAGCACUGAGUAAAUACUUCUUGAAUGAAUAAAACUAGAUUCUAAAAAUCAUUUGAUCAAACGCAACUCCACACUUUCUACUUCUCUUCUUUUAGAACCACACUGUAUUUCUGCUUUUUUUUUUUUUUUUUUUUUUUUUGACAUAGAAUCUCACUCUGUCACCCAGGUUGGAGUGCAGUGGCAUGCAAUCUUGGCUCACUGCAACCUCUGCCUCCUGGGUUCAAGCAGUUCUCCUGCCUUAGCCUCCCAUGUAGCUGGGAUUACAGGUACCCGCCACCAUGCCCAGCUAAUUUUUGUAUUGUUAGUAGAGAUGGAAUUUCACCAUAUUGGCCAGGCUGGUCUUGAACUCCUGACUUCAAGUGAUCCACCCACCUUAGCCUCCCAAAGUGCUAGGAUUACAGGUGUGAGCCACCACUCCCAGCCCCUAUGUCUGCUUUAAGUGGAGAAGCAGAGCUUAUGAGGGAGGAGAACAAGGGUGCAAAAGGGACCUAGAUAUCACUGAGAACUGCCCUUGUUGUUUGGUUGAGGAAAUGGGCCCAGACAGUGGACAAGACUUGCUCAGGGAGACAAACGAGAUGGUGUCCAGUGCAACAAACCUAGGUUUCCUAACUUCCAGUUCUGUCCACUCUACAUCAGUGCCUCUCACCUGUCCCUGCAGGUUCACAUUUUGGUUAUGUGGAUAAGGAGAAAUAAAUUGAAGAUCACAAUGUCCCAUUUUAUCUUCCCCAAGACAAGCUCUGUAACAUUAAAGACCACUAUGCAAACCGAUUACUAGAAAA